AGUUGGGGAGUGGCACUCGCAGCUGCAGCAAAUCUCAAAAUAAAGAGGCAACGGCCUUUCUCUUCCUCUCCAUCUCCCUAUAGCACACCUUUUAUUUCUUUUCUUCUUUUUUUUAAGCCUCACGAAAGAUUUUACUUGUAGAUCAACUUUCAAAAUGUAGGAAGUCAGAAUGGGUGACAUCAUCAGAAAAAUAUGUGGAGCUGAUCACAAGAAGUGAAGAACCCAGAGCACGAAAGCGGUUGUGACUCCUGGGCCCAGGGAGUUGACAGCGUCUGGGUUUCAGAGGAGCCAGCGCCUCCGAGUUGUCUUGAAGUGAGGCUCUGCUGUAGUCCUGUUCUUCUGGCUCUAAGAUCUGAAUGUUGUGACCACUAAUUUGCUCUUUCCUGGAGAGUAACCCCAGUUUGGUCCACAAGGCUUGCUGCCCAAUCUUUGCCAACAGUUGAACCAAGACUCUGAGGCUGAUAUGCAAUGUCACUUACAACAUUAAUCAGAUACUGCAUUUAAGGUUCACAGUGUCUUCACCUGGAAUAGAUUCCACCUCAAGAAACCAGUUUCUUUGCUCAUCCAUAAGAAGCAACUCCUCAUCUGAUCAAGUUUUAUAAUAAGAUUGCAGAAAUUCAGUCUCAUCUUUAGGCUCCACUUCUAGUUCUUAUGCUAUUUCCACCACAUCUGCAGUUACUUCCUCCACUGAAGUCUUGAAUCUCUCAAAGUCAUCCAUGAGGGUUGGAACCAACAUCUUCCAAACUCCUGAUCUUGAUGUGGAAGAAAUGGAGGACUCAGAACCAAGGAUUUCCAAGUGAUUUCUUCCAAAGCACAGGAAUCUCACUCUGUUAAAGCUGGUCUGUUCUAACUGAGCUGGAUGGUCCAGGCCCUAUUUCUAUGAUCUGUUUUUUGGAACUGUUGUAUUUGUGUGACACAGUGAUGGAGCAUGAUGUCAACUCCCACAUACUGUAACCCAGGAAGGAGCAUGAUGUCAGCUCAGGAUACCGGAACCGAUAAAAACUCAGCUGGAGUACAAUGGCGCAAUCUUGGCUCACCACAACCUCCGCCUCCCGGGUUCAAGCAGUUCUUCUCUCUCAGCCUCCCGAGUAGCUGGGAUUACAGGUAUGUGCCACCAUGCCCGGCUAAUUUUGUAUUUUGAGAAGAGACGGGGUUUCACCAUGUUGGUGAGGCUGGUCAUGAACUCCCAACCUCAGGUGAUCCACCUGCCUCGGCCUCCCAAAGUGCUGGGAUUACAGGCAUGAGCCACCACGCCUGGCCCACCCCAUCCCACUUUAUUAGCUGGGAAGUGGAGUCAUCUGUUCUUCCCCAGGCUCUCACUCUGUCUGGGGUGGAUAGCUACUUUUUACCUGGACCACUGUGAUGGCCUAUUGGUCUCCUGCCUGCAGCCUGCCUCCCUCUGAGCCUUUCAGCAUACUGCAGGCUGCGUGAUUUUUUUUUAAAAAAGCUCAAAUUUCAUUAUAACUCUCAAUGGUUCCCUAUUCCCUGCAAUAUAAAAUUUAACUGUAGGGAGUCCUUUAGGGCCCUUUAUGAUCUGGUCUGACCCUUCUUUCCCAAGCUCUCUCAUUCAACAGAUACAUGCUGAGGCCUGCCAUGUGCCUGGCCCCACAUAGACGCUGUCGACUGGGCUGCACACACUACUCCUGCUACCACUCAGACUCCCUCAUUAGCCCCUGAGAACAGUACCCACUUUGAUCAUUUUUAAUUUUUUUUUUUUUUUUGCCUAUAGUGUUCCUUCUGCUUACAGCAUCCUUCCUAUACCCCUGUUUUACUUAUUUAUGGAAGUAAUCCAGGGCCUCUGUAAAUAAUUGUACUUACUCUUCUAACAUUUUAUACUUAUCUCCAGUAUAUGGCCUGCCAUCAUGGAUUCCAAUGAUUAGUUGACAGUUCUCUUUCUUCCCCUAGACUCUGGGCUCCUUGAGAGCAGAGACUUGCCUUCCUCCUGUUCAUAUCUCCAGUAUAACUCUAGCACCCAAGUACUGUGUCUGACCAUAUUAACAUAUUUGCUGGAUAAAGUUGUUAAAAGGUGUGUCAAGAAGGCAAAUCAAGGUGCUACUUAUUAACUAUGAUUUUUAAAGGCUUUCUGACACACAAAGGUAGAUAUCCCCGCUGAAAAAUGUCAUGCUUGGAUUUUGCAAAGUUAUGACAAUAUUUUAAUGACAUAUAUAAUGAUAUUUAUUGUAUAUGUUGUUCUGUUAAGUAUGACUACAAUAUUAUUCCAUGUUAAGAGUUGGCCUUUUGCUAACCAUCCUAGUUGAACAAUCUGAGAGAAGAAUCAGAACCCCACAGAAGUGGUUGGGGCUUUGUAUAUUAUAAAUCUGAGUCAGGACACCCUAGAGUGUUCAUUAGCCUGAUUUGAAAUGCCGUAUUCCGCAAAUGGAAGCAGAGCCUAAAGGGAGGUUCAGGAUGCUGUGAAGCAGAAUGUUUUGGAAGAAGCAGUAGUUUUGAACUGGAAAGACAAAAUAGAUGAUGUCAGCAUAGACCUAAGCCACCUUUUUGAAUCAUAUAGCAUGUGUUUUGUCAGAUCUGAAGCUAUCUAGUCAGGCUGAUAAAGAAUUAAAAUAACAUGUGGGCUUCCAAGAAGCCAAACAUGAUAAAAAUAUAUGAGUCAGGGGAGAAAGGAGAUCCUACAGGGGCCCAGAGCCGAGAGACUUGAAAGAAGGCAAAAGAAACAUCAGCAAAGUAUGCUAUUGAUCUGUGACCCAGUGAAGGACAGACUCCUUCACUCCGGGGUCACCCUUUCUCCCUUCAGGGGCAAAGAGGAAGUCAUAAGAUUCCAUUUCAUUUCAUUCUAGUUUUAUUUGUAGAAAUAAUCCCCCAUACUUCUAGAAAAGAUUCAUGGAAGAUUACAGUUAAAGGCAGGGUAAACAAGAGCAGAAGAACUAAUGUUAAAUAAAGAAAAUGAAACAAUAGGCACACCAGAAACCCAGGCCAAGAAUAGCUACAACAAUUGAUGAUAAAAGUUAGUUCUGAGCUUCUUUGUCUUGAGAAUUAAAACAGAAACAUGGUGAAUAUAGUGUUCUCAUUAUCUGAAUUGAAGAAUUUGUUAGUAGAAAGGUACUUUUUUCCUAUGACUGGAUACAAUAAAAGAAUUUAUCAAAUGGAUCCUUGUAUAAAGGACACUAAAUAACAUAAUAGUCACAGCUUAUAAUAGCAGCUUUACAAAAAGGUAGAGAGGUUCUUUGUGUGGCCAUCUGGUCCAUCCAACUAAAUAAAUGCCAUGAGCUAAAUGUUAUACUUUACUGCUAGGAAAACAUUGCCACUGAGAGUUAAAGAAGUAUCAUCAAACUGUAAGGCUUUCUGGAGACGUCUCUUAAUACAGAAUAGCACAGAGAGACUGGAUGAAUCUCUGAUGACAGUCAUGUCCCUUUCCAGGGACCUCAAGGACGACUUUCACAGUGACACGGUACUCUCCAUCUUAAAUGAGCAGCGCAUUCGGGGCAUUUUAUGCGAUGUCACUAUCAUUGUGGAAGAUACCAAAUUUAAAGCCCAUAGCAAUGUUCUGGCAGCUUCAAGCCUGUAUUUUAAAAAUAUCUUUUGGAGCCAUACAAUCUGUAUUUCCAGCCACGUCCUGGAGCUGGACGAUCUCAAAGCUGAAGUGUUUACUGAAAUACUUAAUUAUAUCUACAGUUCCACAGUCGUUGUCAAGAGACAGGAAACAGUCACUGAUCUCGCAGCUGCAGGAAAAAAGCUGGGAAUAUCGUUCUUGGAAGACCUUACUGAUCGCAACUUCUCAAAUUCCCCGGGUCCCUAUGUAUUCUGUAUUACUGAAAAGGGAGUGGUUAAAGAAGAAAAAAAUGAAAAAAGGCAUGAAGAACCAGCCAUCACUAAUGGGCCAAGGAUCACAAAUGCAUUUUCCAUCAUCGAAACAGAAAAUAGUAAUAACAUGUUUUCCCCGCUGGACUUGAGGGCAAGUUUCAAAAAGGUCUCCGACUCCAUGAGAACAGCUAGCCUUUGCCUGGAGAGGACGGACGUCUGCCACGAGGCAGAGCCUGUCCGCACACUUGCCGAGCACUCAUACGCUGUUUCUUCCGUAGCUGAAGCUUACAGAAGUCAGCCUGUACGUGAACAUGAUGGCAGUUCACCUGGUAACACAGGGAAAGAAAAUUGUGAAGCCCUUGCAGCGAAACCGAAAACAUGCCGGAAGCCAAAGACAUUCUCCAUACCACAGGAUUCGGAUUCAGCCACAGAAAAUAUACCACCCCCUCCAGUAUCCAACUUAGAGGUUAAUCAAGAAAGAAGUCCACAACCAGCUGCUGUUCUCACUCGUUCAAAAUCUCCAAACAAUGAAGGAGAUGUCCAUUUUUCCAGGGAAGAUGAAAAUCAAUCUUCUGAUGUUCCCGGGCCGCCAGCCGCAGAGGUUCCACCUCUGGUGUACAAUUGUAGCUGCUGUUCCAAAGCCUUUGACAGCAGCACUCUGCUCAGUGCCCACAUGCAGCUUCACAAGCCAACCCAGGAGCCUUUAGUGUGCAAGUAUUGCAACAAACAAUUCACCACCCUGAACAGGUUGGAUCGGCAUGAACAGAUCUGCAUGAGGUCAAGCCACAUGCCCAUUCCUGGAGGAAACCAACGCUUUUUAGAAAACUAUCCUACCAUUGGACAAAAUGGAGGUUCAUUCACAGGUCCAGAACCUUUAUUAUCUGAAAAUAGGAUUGGUGAAUUUUCCAGUACCGGAAGUACUUUGCCAGACACGGACCACAUGGUUAAAUUUGUUAAUGGGCAAAUGCUCUACAGUUGCGUUGUGUGCAAACGUAGUUAUGUGACCUUAUCUAGCCUCCGAAGACAUGCAAAUGUUCACUCCUGGAGAAGAACAUAUCCUUGCCAUUACUGCAACAAAGUAUUUGCAUUGGCUGAGUACAGGACAAGGCAUGAAAUUUGGCAUACGGGAGAAAGACGAUAUCAGUGCAUUUUCUGUCUUGAAACUUUCAUGACCUACUAUAUACUCAAAAAUCAUCAGAAGUCUUUCCAUGCCAUCGAUCAUAGACUUUCCAUCAGUAAAAAAACAGCAAAUGGAGGCUUGAAGCCUAGUGUCUAUCCGUAUAAACUUUAUAGGCUACUGCCUAUGAAAUGCAAGAGAGCCCCUUAUAAGAGCUACCGAAAUUCUUCCUAUGAAAAUGCACGAGAAAACAGUCAAAUGAAUGAGUCUGCACCUGGUACCUAUGUUGUUCAGAAUCCACACAGCUCUGAAUUACCAACGCUGAAUUUCCAAGAUACUGUAAACACCCUGACCAACAGUCCAGCCAUCCCAUUGGAAACAUCUGCAUGUCAGGACAUACCCACUUCUGCCAAUGUACAAAAUGCAGAGGGUACCAAAUGGGGAGAGGAGGCAUUGAAAAUGGAUCUUGACAAUAACUUUUAUUCAACUGAGGUGUCAGUUUCUUCCACUGAAAAUGCUGUCAGUUCUGACCUCCGGGCAGGGGAUGUACCUGUUUUAUCUUUGAGUAAUAGCAGUGAGAAUGCCGCCUCUGUGAUCAGCUACAGUGGCUCUGCACCCUCGGUCAUUGUACACAGCAGCCAGUUUUCAUCGGUGAUCAUGCACAGCAAUGCCAUUGCUGCCAUGACCAGCAGCAACCACAGAGCCUUUUCAGACCCAGCUGUCAGUCAGUCCCUGAAAGAUGACAGUAAGCCCGAGCCAGAUAAAGUGGGUAGGUUUGCAAGCAGACCCAAAAGCAUUAAGGAGAAAAAGAAAACUACAUCACAUACCAGGGGAGAAAUACCGGAGGAGUCAAACUAUGUUGCUGAUCCUGGAGGAUCACUGAGCAAAACCACAAAUAUUGCUGAAGAAACCAGCAAAAUUGAAACCUACAUUGCAAAACCUGCUCUGCCGGGAACCUCCACAAAUAGUAAUGUUGCACCCCUUUGCCAAAUAACAGUGAAAAUUGGAAACGAAGCCAUUGUGAAAAGGCACAUUCUAGGAUCUAAAUUGUUUUAUAAAAGAGGGAGAAGACCCAAGUAUCAGAUGCAGGAGGAGCCUUUGCCACAGGGGAAUGACCCAGAACCCAGUGGAGACAGCCCACUCGGGCUUUGCCAAUCCGAGUGCAUGGAGAUGAGUGAAGUGUUCGAUGACGCAAGUGACCAGGAUUCCACUGACAAACCGUGGCGCCCUUACUACAACUACAAACCCAAAAAGAAAUCCAGACAGUUGAAAAAAAUGAGGAAAGUCAACUGGAGGAAGGAGCACGGAAACAGGAGCCCGAGCCAUAAAUGUAAAUACCCAGCAGAACUGGAUUGCGCCGUGGGGAAGGCUCCUCAGGAUAAACCCUUUGAGGAAGAAGAAACUAAAGAGAUGCCCAAGCUGCAGUGUGAACUCUGUGAUGGAGACAAAGCAGUGGGGGCUGGAAACCAAGGAAGGCCCCACCGACAUCUUACUUCUCGGCCAUAUGCCUGCGAGCUCUGCGCCAAGCAGUUCCAGAGCCCUUCCACACUCAAAAUGCACAUGAGAUGUCACACCGGGGAGAAGCCAUACCAGUGCAAGACCUGCGGACGGUGCUUUUCGGUGCAAGGAAACUUACAGAAACAUGAACGCAUCCACCUGGGCUUGAAGGAGUUCGUCUGUCAGUAUUGCAACAAGGCAUUCACCUUGAAUGAGACCCUCAAAAUCCAUGAAAGAAUCCAUACUGGAGAAAAGCGUUACCACUGUCAGUUCUGCUUUCAGAGAUUUUUGUAUCUCUCCACCAAAAGGAAUCACGAGCAGAGGCAUAUUCGGGAGCAUAAUGGGAAGGGCUAUGCCUGCUUCCAGUGCCCCAAAAUUUGCAAAACAGCUGCUGCCCUUGGAAUGCACCAAAAGAAACACUUAUUCAAAAGCCCAAGUCAGCAGGAGAAAAUAGGUGACGUGUGCCACGAAAACUCAAAUCCCUUGGAGAAUCAACAUUUCAUUGGUUCAGAAGACAAUGACCAAAAGGAUAACAUACAAACCGGUGUGGAAAAUGUUGUCCUUUGAGUGGCAAGAAUUAGAAAAAUCUUCAAAAAUAUAGUUGGUGGUUUUUUUAGUUAUGAUUUAAGUUUAGUUUCAUUUUGUCCAUGUGACAGUCAUGAAGGAGUGAAAUUAAAAAAAAAAAAAACUCAUUUGUGAAAAUUCCAGAAAAAGGAUCCUAAUAUCUACUUUGGGUUUUAGCAUUAACUUUAUGCAAAGUGCACAAAAACAAAAUAGCUGACUCCUCCAAUAUCCCAAGUUUCUUGUGAAAGUUAAUAAAAUUCUUAGCUGUGGUAUUUCUACCAGUGAAAAAAGGAGUUUAAUUUUAGCCUAGUUUAAAACUUUCUAAUAAUUGCUAAUAAGAACUGGCUGCUGAACUGUCUUUAGUCACUGGAGAAAAUAAGGGUCAGAUAUCCUGAAGAUGGCAUCUUCGUAAAUAUGUUACGUGGUAAUAAGCUGUGUGACGGUCUUUAUUCCCAUCUGGCUUCUGCACUAUUAAAAUUUGUUUAAAUUAAUGGAUACACAUGAAAUACUUAAACAAUAUAACUGAAAUUAUGUGCAUAAUGAGUAACCUAAAGUAGGACAUUCAUACAUUAUGUAGAACUACUUUUCUGCAACACAAACCUUGUAAAAUACAUAUAUAAAUCACUAUAACUUUUAACUGUCCAUAUCCCCUGUAGAGAAUUAUGAGGAGCAAUAGAUCUGCAAAUAAUGAGGACUGAUGUAAAAAUCAAUAGAAAGCAUUUUGAAUAUGAUUUAAGAGCAUGUGAAUGCUUUUAGAUGGAAUGCUGUUCCCUUGAAGUUAUGGCUGAGCUGUUCUUAGAACUGGUCUACUCAAUUCACAGAAAACAUAGGUCAUGCCUUAUCUAUGGGGGAACACCCUCCCAGAAUUUACCUGUGAUUACCUGUGCUGCAUAUUACUUUGCAAUGGCCUCAUCUCAGAGAAUGAAAGAGGGUCACAUUGUUCUGAAACUCUCUGCAGUCUUCCAACCACCACAAGGCCAUGGAUGUGGGGGUCUAUUCCAGACAGACUUAAGGGCUCAAGUGGAACCUGCCAUCUCCCAUUCCACUGAAGGACUGUCCAAGAGAUUUAGUGCAAGGUACACUGCAGUAGUGAAUUCCCAGGCACUUGAAAGUGACUGCCUAAUCCCUACAAUUACUAGCCUUGUUGGAGAUUAUGCAGCCCACAAGUACAGACUAGUAUAAAGCAAAAGGACAAAGGAACCCCCACCCUCCACCCCACCCAUUAAUGACUUGAGUGGGCAAGAAGAAGUGAUGGCCUUCCUUGCCUAAAACAGUAGCUUUGUUUUUAGGGGGUGGGAAGGUAGGAUGUGGAGUGACAUGGUUCUAUCCUUUACUUAUGAGACUCAGAAAUAUAUCUACAAAGCCAGAUGCUCUGUCUUCAUAUUUGCAGACAUCUAGACCCCUUGCUAAAAACCCACUGAAGUUUUUUUUUUAUGUUCUUUGACCCACACCAUCAACACUACCCUCAAAUCUAAUUGCCCUACAGCAUAUUCUAUCAUGUGGACUAGGUUCCUGGAAAGCCGGAACUCAUGAUUCUUUUUCAAACUGCCAGAAUAGAAGGGAGAGAGAAAACAUUUCUACCCUUUGAUCACCAGUGUGAACAGAAUCCGGAAUGCAGUUUCAGCGUGACCUGCAGUCAUUCAUGUUCAUUGGAUUUGACAGAUGGAAACCCAAGGUUAUCGAAGAUUGGAAGGUUAUCAUUGUGAAGAAGUAGCUCAAAGGACUCCGGUUUCUGUCUACAAGUGUGAUGUCUCCAUGAAGAAGACUUAGUAUGGAUUUGGGUGGGUAAGAAAGCAUUUAAACGCCCAGGAAAGGACAUGAUUAAAGUUGACCUUUUAAUACUGUAGUACCUUGCUGUUAAGUAACCCCACUAUUGUAUCUGCAUUUAUCUUUUGUUCAUCUACUUUCACUUACAUACAGUAUUAUAUAAGUAGAGAAAAAUGGGAAAAUGCAAGCAAAUUCAACUUUAUUUUAUACAUUGUAUAUAUGUACACCCUACACUAUUCAUUUGGGUUUUAUUAAAGAGAUAGUCACAAAGGGCUUACGAAAAUCAUUUUUGAAUUGAUAAUUAGAAUAUUGAAUAAGCAAUCCUAUGAUCCACUAAUUUGUUUUAUCAGUUAAUAAUAUUAAUCAAAGACAUUUACUGUAUAUUCUAGUCAUUUUGAUUUGAGUUAACCCCAAAUAUAAAAUUACCUGUAGUGAUGUCUCUCUCCCAGCCCUUAUAUGUGGAUAUUUUUUAAGUGGACUUGUAUGCUGAUAAUUCUAGACCAAAGUAAAUAUGGCAGAAUAUUUAUACAUGAAAAAAUAAUUUUGCAAAUAUUUUCUAUAAUUGUAUUCAUUUAAAAUGUUGAUAGCUUGUGUUAGUUUCAGGGAGGGGUGUAUAUUUUGAUAAAAAAAUACUUGACUUUGUAAUUCUGUAUAUUCUAUACAAUUUAUAGCAGAGCCGUUUUAAGACAGCCUUGUCACAUUUUUUUGUUAAUUGUGAAAAUUUUAUUGAGUGAUGUUUAAGUAUGCAUUGAGUACAUGACCAACUAGAAUUAAAGUAAGUGUAAACAGUGAACAUACUGUAUGCUGUACAAGAUAUAAUGUAACUUGCUGUUUUAGCAUCUGUAUUUUGGUUAGAAGAUAUUAUUAAAUGCAGAUGUUAAGGAUUGGAAAAGUCUAAUUUUAUUUUUAGAAAUAAUGGAUAUAAAUUUGUUUUUGCUUGAUUAAAAUAGCUUAUUCCUACAUUAAGUCUCUUUUUAAAUGUUUUCAUGUUAUUUCUUUUGUGCAGCUAUUUCAUCUGUGUGAGUCACAGCUUUGUUUCCACGUAUUAUUCAGUUUAUUUCUGUUUCCUUACUUGUUUACAUUCCGUGGUACCUACUUACAUGCUUAGGAGUCAAAUGGAUUAUGACAUUAGGAAAAAAGCAGAAUAAAAGAGAUUGAAGUCUUCUGAUGAUUGAGUGUUUUGGAUAGGCCUGAUCUUAUAAUGAUAAAUCAGAGAAUGAAAUGCUCUCCAGGAAGCAUUCUGCUCCACUCAUCCGUGGGAAACAAAUUACAUUUAUUGAGUACCAGGCACUGGGCAAUGUCUUUACAUAGGCUAUUUCAUUAACACACACGCACCAGAAUUCGACCUCAUUAUCCUCGUUUUAUAGUGACUUUGAGAAGGUCUCACAACCAGACAAAGCCAGGAUGCUAACCUAGGUCUGCCUGACUCCAAAGCCCAUGUUUUUGUUCCUUCUCAACACUGUAGAGAAAAAUCAUUUAUAGAAACUGAACAGAGUAUGAGGAAAGGAGAUAUGAUAAAGUAAUGCAGCUUUAGGAUGGCAGUUAGUGACUGCCCUGGAACAGGAUUAAAGGAGGCUGUGUCAGGUUCAGCUUCCCCUGAAUUGGGCUUCCCUUAUAUCUCAGGAGAUUGCCCUAUAAAAUCAGUAAAAUUUGUGCACUUUUUUAAGGAUAUGGAGUAAAAUUGUAAUAGCAUUAUAAGCUGGUAAUUUUCACACAAAGAAAAAAAUACGUUCCGUCGUCACAGACUCUACUCCUAAACUUAGCUAACUAACUAUCUUGCAAAUGCCUGCAGUUUGUCCCAGUGGGCAAUGUGAGAGGGGAUGUCGGUGGCUCAGGCAGCACAGUCCAUCACCAACACAGAGAAAAUUACUGCCAGGCCUACCGGUGGCUGGCCAGUAGCAUCAAUUUUGUAUUGGAAGGGCAAUCCAAACCAGAUUCACCAAAAAUUUGAUAACUGUUAUCUGCUAAAACUAACUUCAUUAUGUACAAGAACAACAGAUUUAAUAUUGAAAGCAUCUGUAACAAUUGGGAAAGUAAAAGCAUAAAACAAAA